GCCGCGGCGCCGAGCUACGGGUGCCGGGUGGAGCGAAGCACGGAAUGUGUCUCCUGCUGGGGGCCACGGGCGUCGGGAAGACGCUGCUGGUGAAACGGCUGCAGGAGGUGAGCUCCCGGGAUGGGAAAGGCGACCUGGGGGAGCCGCCCCCGACACGGCCCACGGUGGGCACCAAUCUUACUGACAUCGUGGCACAGAGAAAGAUCACCAUCCGGGAGCUUGGGGGGUGCAUGGGCCCCAUCUGGUCCAGUUACUAUGGAAACUGCCGUUCUCUCCUGGCCUGUGCCGCGGAUACCAGUAUGGAGAACUGAUGGCCACAUGAGGACAGAGACGAGUGACACCAGGUCGUCUUCAUAAAACUCGAUUCCCUCUGCUUCUGCUUGUUCCCAAAGCUUUGUUUAAAGCUACUUUGGGCCGGGCGCGGUGGCUUACUCCUGUAAUCCCAGCACUUUGGGAAGCUGAGGUGGGCGAAUCACGAGGUCAGGAGAUGGAGACCAUCCUGACUAACAUGGUGAAACCCCGUCUCUACUAAAAGUACAAAAAAUUAGCCAGGCGUGGUGGCGGGUGUCUGUAGUCCCAGUUACUUGGGAGGCUGAGGCAGGAGAAUCACUUGAACCCUGAACCCUGGAGGCGGAGUUUCAGUGAGCCGAGAUCGUGCCACUGCACUCGGAGCGAGACUUCGUCUCAAAAAAUAAAUUAAUUAAUUAAAAAAUGCAGUUUUGCUCUCCCAGUGCCAGGUCUGUGAGGCCCAGGGGAGGAAGUUUGGCAGCGGGGCAUUGCUGCUGUCUUUUUCUUUUUCCCCAGUUUGUGAUGGACGCCUCUGACCCCACCCAGCUCUCUGCAUCCUGUGUGCAGCUCUUAGGUCUCCUUUCUGCAGAACAACUUGCAGAAGCAUCGGUGCUGAUACUCUUCAAUAAAAUCGACCUACCCUGUUACAUGUCCACGGAGGAGAUGAAGUCAUUAAUCAGGCUUCCAGACAUCAUUGCUUGUGCCAAGCAGAACAUCACCACGGCAGAAAUCAGCGCCCGUGAAGGCACUGGCUUAGCAGGGGUGCUGGCCUGGCUCCAGGCCACCCACAGAGCCAACGAUUGACUGCACGGCAGAGGCGCAGCUGGCCUGAGCUGGGGAGAGGUGGCAGAGGGCAGUAUGGCUUUGCUGCCAAUAGUUUCUUCUCACAGGGGCAGAAUAACCCAAAGUAACCCUACAUGAUGGGGCUCUGUGCUGAGAUGCAAUGAUGUGUAAACUGAGGCAUGUGGAGAUGGAAGUUGACAUCUGGCCUCUGAAAAAAGUGUCCCCAGGGGCUAGGCAUGGUGGCUCACACCUGUAAUCCCAGCACUUUGAGAGGCCGAGGCGGGUGUAUCACCUGAGGUCGGGAGUUCGAGACUAGCCUGACCAACAUGGAGAAACCCUGUCUCUACUAAAAAUACAAAAUUAGCUGGGUGUGCUGGUGCAUGCCUGUAAUCUCAGCUACUUGGGAGGCUGAGACAGGAGAAUCCCUUGAACCUGGGAGGUGGAGGUUGCAGUGAGUCGAGAUCAUGCCAUUGCACUGCACCUGGGCAACAAGAGUGAAACUCCGUCUUAAAAAAUAUAAGAAAUAAAAAAAUAAAAACCUG